UGUGCCAAAUCAUUCACCCCUCACCACAACCGAAUGAGCUAAGGAUUCUCAUUAUAUAUAGUUUAUGGAGAGGGAAGUGCAGACAUAAAGAGGUGAAUUGUCUUACCCAGAUCACACAGCUGAUAAGUGGUGGAGGCAGAAUAGAAUCUAAACAGUGUGGCUCCGGAGCCCACAUGCAUUGAUUCGACAAGUGUUUAUUGAGCACCUGCCACGGACAAGGCCUUGUGUGAUUAAAUAGGGUUAUAAUUAGUAAUAUAAAAAUGAGAAAUCACUAAUGCUUUUUAGACUUAACAUUUUCUUUUUUUGUAGGUUUCAGGCACAGAACUGUAUAUCCAAUAAUAGUGAAAUGGAUCCCACUAAUUAUGACAGAAAUGAUGAUACAUUUAAAUGACUUGGAUGUUUUAUAGGUAUGAUCUCGUGAAACCUUGAGAGAAACUGAAUGACGAAUGAAACUAUUGUUCCUGUUUCACACAGAAGAAAACUGAGUUCCUGUCGCAUGACCAGAGCCAGCUCACCAAGGAGCUGCAGCAGCAUGUAAAGUCAGUGACAUGCCCAUGCGAGUACCUGAGGAAGAUGAUCCUACACCUGCCACCUCCGAUGGAUCCACUGCCUCUGUGCCUGCCUGUACUGCUGAUGCUCCAGUGGAUAACUCAGCAUCCCAGCCUAGGCCCAAUGCCACUGAAGAUGGACCUGCACCCUGGGGACCCAGGAGUCCUACCACUCAGCUGUCCCCAGGAGUGCCCAGACCCUCAUUCUUAUCCAGGACCUAGGAGCCCUACCCCUGGCCUUCCCUCAUCAGCCGUAAAUGAUGAUUUACUGCUGUUACCAUCAUCACUGCCUUCAGUGACCAAGGGCCUUCCAAGGUGCCAGCUCUGGAACGAAAGAUGCCCUUGGGAGGUGAUGACACUCAGGUACACGGGUGCUCAACAGAUUGCUUCCUCCUAUCCUCAGACGGUCUUUGCAUGCAUGCAGCCAUUGGCACUCCCAUUGUAUGGAAGGAAACCAGCCCAGGGUCACACAGCUGGUCAGCAGCAACAUAGCUGGUCUCAAAUCUAAGGUGCCUGGCCAUGCCUCCAUGAGGGACCGCCUGCAAGGGAGGUUGAUCCUGGCUUUGGGGAGCCUUUCCUGGGCUGCACGAAUAACCUCCAUUGUUCGAGACCCCAAACUCUGCUCACAUCUUCCUUUCCCUGUCUCUGCUUGGGCUAUGAUCACGGUGACUCUAGCAACCCUUCAUGGACAUUAUAGUACUCUCUGCCAUUCACUUUUGGUCUAAUCUGACUUCAACCCCCACUUACUUGGUCUCUCCUUUUACAACCAACACAACCGAAAUCUAGGGCUUUUUUUUUUUUUUUUCUUUUUGAGACAGAGUCUCAUUCCAUUCUGUUACCCAGGCUGGAGUGCAAUGGUACGAUCUCGGCUCACUGCAACCUCCGCCUCCCGGGUCCAAGGGAUUGUCCUGCCUCAGCCUCCUGAGUAGCUGGGAUUACAGGCGGGUGCCACCAUGCCUGGCUAAUUUUUGUAUUUUUAGUAGAGACAGGGUUUCACCAUGUUGGUCAGGCUGGUCUCGAACUCCUAACCUCGUGAUCCGCCUGCCUCAGCCUCCCAAAGUGCUGGGAUUACAGGCGUGAGCCACCAUGCCCAGCCAAAUCUAGGGCUGGAACAUGGCUGCAGCAUAUAAAUAGAAUUGAAUUCCAUAGUUUUGUUAACCCUGUUUUUUGUUUGUUUGUAGUUGUUGCUGUUUUUGAGACAAGAGUCUCUCUCUGUCGCCUAGUCUGGAGUGCAGUGGUGCAAUCUCGGCUCACUGCAGACUCUGCCUCCCGGGUUCAAACUAUUCUCCUGCCUCAGCCUCCCAAGUAGGUGGGACUAAGGCGCCCACCACCACACCCGGCUAAUUUUUAUAUUUUAUUAGAGACAGGGUUUCACCAUAUUGGCCAGGCUGGUCUGGAACUCCUGACCUUGUGAUCCGCCGACCUCGGCCUCCCAAAGUGCUGGGAUUACAGGCGUGAGCCACCACACCCAGCCCCUGUUUUGUUUUUGUUUUGCUUGUUUCUUAGGGUUGUUUUUCUAUUUAUGGUAAAGGCAUUGGCUUUCCAUUUGUAGCAUCAAUAGAAUAUUUCCUGUUUACAAUAACCUUAUGUCAUAGUAAAUGGUAAAGGGAUUUAAAGCAGUGGUUUUCAGCUCCCAGAGGCCUGAGUGAGUUUGGGCACACUCUGUGUGAUCAGGCAGAAGGCCUGUGGGAAGUUUAGCUGAGGACAGGGCCAGGAAAGGUGAUGGACAGUGGGGGUCUGUCCUGGUCACCAGACCCCUGCGUCCUGCCCACCUGCUUGGAGCUCCCCACCCAUCACACAUGAUGCUGCCAAGCCCUCUGGGUAUUGUGGGCAAAUACCUUAGGAGAGAAGCUGAUGAACUUUGUUUCUUGAAAUGCACAGAUUCCUUGGACAUCCCUGAGAGGUCAAUCAUGAAGGUCAACUUGGUUUUCUCCCCCUCAUUUGGGUUCAGAAUUUAAAGUCCACACACACAGGCAGUAAGAUGAUUAUAGAUAAGGACAUCAUCACUCGGUUUCGGAUGUUAAAAUGUCUAGGUGGGUUAGGGGUGAUUUGAGAUCACACAACCUUGUGCCACAAAGAGGAAUUCCCAGGCCAGAGGGAGACAUUUUAUUGCCAUGUUAUGAUCUUAUCAUUGAGUUGAAAGGCAAUCUUGUUUCAUUUUGGAUUCUUUCUUAUGUUUAUGUCUUAUAAGGGCACUUUGAAUUUCCAAGCAAAUAAUAAUUUUGAAUUAGCUUUUAAUCAUUGACUUCUAGCACAGUUAUAUGAUCAGAAACGUGCUGUGUGAUUUGAUUGCUCUCAAAUAUAUUGAGAUUUGCUGGAACAAAAUAAGUCAGGUUAAUUUUUGUAAAUGUACCAUGCAUGCUUAAAAUGAAUGUAUCUACAUUUGUUCCUGAGAUACAGGUUGAUGGACGGAUGGCUACAUGGAUGUGAUGGAGAUGGUUUACUAUCGGGACCUUCCGCAUCCUGCUGAUGUUUUGUUGCUUAGGAUAUGAAUGGCUGAGCGGAGGCUGUAAAACCUGGCACUCUGCUUGGGUAUGAGGUUCUUCCUGCCAUCCUGCCAUCAUUUGUUUUUUAUGUUUUGUCGCCAAAAGUGACCUUGAGGAACCCUGGGAGCUCAGGAAGGAAGGAGCGCCCAGAAGCAGGGACAGGGAGCUGGUUGGGGAGGACCAGAAAUCAGGGCACCCUGAAAGGAUCAUGACAUGCGGCUGCGCUUUUGGCUCCUCAUUUGGCUCCUGCUGGGAUUUAUCAGCCAUCAGCCCACCCCUGUUAUCAAUAGUCUGGCUGUCUAUCGUCAUCGUGAGACUGACUUUGGUGUAGGAGUUCGAGACCACCCUGGCCAACAUGGCAAAACCCCAUCUCCACAAAAAUUGGAUAAUUUGAUAAUUAUCAUUAUUGGGUUUCUGAGACGUUACACAUUUAACAUUCUCUUCUGCACAAGUUGCCUUUGUGUGUCUUUCCUGAAGACUAUCUUCUGGUCUCGAAAUGGACAUGAUGGAUCCAUGGAUGUACAGCAGAGAGCCUGGAGGUCCAACCGCAGUAGACAGAAAGGGCUGAGGUCCAUUUGUAUGCACACAAAGAAAAGAGUUUCUUCCUUUCGAGGAAAUAAAAUUGGCCUGAAAGACGUCAUUACUCUACGGAGGCAUGUGGAAACAAAAGUUAGAGCUAAAAUCCGUAAGAGGAAGGUGACAACGAAAAUCAACCGUCAUGACAAAAUCAAUGGAAAGAGGAAGACCGCCAGAAAACAGAAAAUGUUUCAACGUGCGCAAGAGUUGCGGCGGCGGGCAGAGGACUACCACAAAUGCAAAAUCCCCCCUUCUGCAAGAAAGCCUCUUUGCAACUGGGUCAGAAUGGUGGCAGCGGAGCAUCGUCAUUCUUCAGGAUUGCCCUACUGGCCCUACCUCACAGCUGAAACUUUAAAAAACAGGAUGGGCCGCCAGCCACCUCCUCCAACUCAACAACAUUCUAUAACUGAUAACUCCCUGAGCCUCAAGACACCUACUGAGUGUCUGCUCACUCCCCUUCCACCCUCAGUGGAUGAUAAUAUCAAGGAGUGUCCUCUUGCUCCUCUUCCACCCUCUCCUCUUCCACCCUCAGUGGAUGAUAAUCUGAAGGAAUGUCUCUUUGUCCCGCUUCCACCCUCUCCUCUUCCACCCUCAGUGGAUGAUAAUCUCAAGACUCCUCCCUUAGCUACUCAGGAGGCCGAGGUGGAAAAACCACCCAAACCCAAGAGGUGGAGGGUGGAUGAGGUGGAACAAUCACCGAAACCCAAGAGGCGGAGGGUGGAUGAGGUGGAACAAUCGCCCAAGCCCAAGAGGCAGAGGGAGGCCGAGGCACAACAAUUACCCAAACCCAAGAGGCGGAGGUUGAGUAAGCUGAGAACACGCCAUUGCACUCAAGCCUGGGCAAUAAGAAUAAAUCCGUAGGUCGAAAAAAAGAAAAAAAUCAAAAAACAAAACAAAACCCACGCUCCAAAAACAAACUAACGAAGAAUAAAUAAAUAAUAUAAAAAUAAA